CUCCUUCCCUGUCUCUGCCUCUCCCUCCCUUCCUCAGGCAUCAGAGCGGAGACUUCAGGGAGACCAGAGCCCAGCUUGCCAGGCACUGAGCUAGAAGCCCUGCCAUGGCACCCCUGAGACCCCUUCUCAUACUGGCCCUGCUGGCAUGGGUUGCUCUGGCUGACCAAGAGUCAUGCAAGGGCCGCUGCACUGAGGGCUUCAACGUGGACAAGAAGUGCCAGUGUGACGAGCUCUGCUCUUACUACCAGAGCUGCUGCACAGACUAUACGGCUGAGUGCAAGCCCCAAGUGACUCGCGGGGAUGUGUUCACUAUGCCGGAGGAUGAGUACACGGUCUAUGACGAUGGCGAGGAGAAAAACAAUGCCACUGUCCAUGAACAGGUGGGGGGCCCCUCCCUGACCUCUGACCUCCAGGCCCAGUCCAAAGGGAAUCCUGAGCAGACACCUGUUCUGAAACCUGAGGAAGAGGCCCCUGCGCCUGAGGUGGGCGCCUCUAAGCCUGAGGGGAUAGACUCAAGGCCUGAGACCCUUCAUCCAGGGAGACCUCAGCCCCCAGCAGAGGAGGAGCUGUGCAGUGGGAAGCCCUUCGACGCCUUCACCGACCUCAAGAACGGUUCCCUCUUUGCCUUCCGAGGGCAGUACUGCUAUGAACUGGACGAAAAGGCAGUGAGGCCUGGGUACCCCAAGCUCAUCCGAGAUGUCUGGGGCAUCGAGGGCCCCAUCGAUGCCGCCUUCACCCGCAUCAACUGUCAGGGGAAGACCUACCUCUUCAAGGGUAGUCAGUACUGGCGCUUUGAGGAUGGUGUCCUGGACCCUGAUUACCCCCGAAAUAUCUCUGACGGCUUCGAUGGCAUCCCGGACAACGUGGAUGCAGCCUUGGCCCUCCCUGCCCAUAGCUACAGUGGCCGGGAGCGGGUCUACUUCUUCAAGGGGAAACAGUACUGGGAGUACCAGUUCCAGCACCAGCCCAGUCAGGAGGAGUGUGAAGGCAGCUCCCUGUCGGCUGUGUUUGAACACUUUGCCAUGAUGCAGCGGGACAGCUGGGAGGACAUCUUCGAGCUUCUCUUCUGGGGCAGAACCUCUGCUGGUACCAGACAGCCCCAGUUCAUUAGCCGGGACUGGCACGGUGUGCCAGGGCAAGUGGACGCAGCCAUGGCUGGCCGCAUCUACAUCUCAGGCAUGGCACCCCGCCCCUCCUUGGCCAAGAAACAAAGGUUUAGGCAUCGCAACCGCAAAGGCUACCGUUCACAACGAGGCCACAGCCGUGGCCGCAACCAGAACUCCCGCCGGCCAUCCCGCGCCACGUGGCUGUCCUUGUUCUCCAGUGAGGAGAGCAACUUGGGAGCCAACAACUAUGAUGACUACAGGAUGGACUGGCUUGUGCCUGCCACCUGUGAACCCAUCCAGAGUGUCUUCUUCUUCUCUGGAGACAAGUACUACCGAGUCAAUCUUCGCACACGGCGAGUGGACACUGUGGACCCUCCCUACCCACGCUCCAUCGCUCAGUACUGGCUGGGCUGCCCAGCUCCUGGCCAUCUGUAGGAGUCAGAGCCCACAUGGCCGGGCCCUCUGUAGCUCCCUCCUCCCAUCUCCUUCCCCCAGCCCAAUAAAGGUCCCUUAGCCCCGA